AGAAAUUACCAAGAAAGCCUGGACCCCGGGUGAAACGGAGAAAUGGACACAAGUCCCCUGUGUUUCUCCAUUCUGUUGGUUUUAUGCAUCUUUAUCCAAUCAAGUGCCCUUGGACAAAGCCUGAAACCAGAGCCAUUUGGAAGAAGAGCUCAAGCUGUUGAAACAAACAAAACGCUGCAUGAGAUGAAGACCAGAUUCCUGCUCUUUGGAGAAACCAAUCAGGGCUGUCAGAUUCGAAUCAAUCAUCCGGACACGUUACAGGAGUGCGGCUUCAACUCCUCCCUGCCUCUGGUGAUGAUAAUCCACGGGUGGUCGGUGGACGGCGUGCUAGAAAACUGGAUCUGGCAGAUGGUGGCCGCGCUGAAGUCUCAGCCGGCCCAGCCAGUGAACGUGGGGCUGGUGGACUGGAUCACCCUGGCCCACGACCACUACACCAUCGCCGUCCGCAACACCCGCCUUGUGGGCAAGGAGGUCGCGGCUCUUCUCCGGUGGCUGGAGGAAUCUGUGCAACUCUCUCGAAGCCAUGUUCACCUAAUUGGGUACAGCCUGGGUGCACACGUGUCAGGAUUUGCCGGCAGUUCCAUCGGUGGAACGCACAAGAUUGGGAGAAUCACAGGGCUGGAUGCCGCGGGACCUUUGUUUGAGGGAAGUGCCCCCAGCAAUCGUCUUUCUCCAGAUGAUGCCAAUUUUGUGGAUGCCAUUCAUACCUUUACCCGGGAGCACAUGGGCCUGAGCGUGGGCAUCAAACAGCCCAUAGGACACUAUGACUUCUAUCCCAACGGGGGCUCCUUCCAGCCUGGCUGCCACUUCCUAGAGCUCUACAGACAUAUUGCCCAGCACGGCUUCAAUGCCAUCACCCAGACCAUAAAAUGCUCCCACGAGCGAUCGGUGCACCUUUUCAUCGACUCCUUGCUGCACGCCGGCACGCAGAGCAUGGCCUACCCGUGUGGUGACAUGAACAGCUUCAGCCAGGGCCUGUGCCUGAGCUGCAAGAAGGGCCGCUGCAACACGCUGGGCUACCACGUCCGCCAGGAGCCGCGGAGCAAGAGCAAGAGGCUCUUCCUCGUAACGCGAGCCCAGUCCCCCUUCAAAGUUUAUCAUUACCAGUUCAAGAUCCAGUUCAUCAACCAAACUGAGACACCAAUACAAACAACUUUUACCAUGUCACUACUCGGAACAAAAGAGAAAAUGCAGAAAAUUCCCAUCACUCUGGGCAAAGGAAUUGCUAGUAAUAAAACGUAUUCCUUUCUUAUCACGCUGGAUGUGGAUAUCGGCGAGCUGAUCAUGAUCAAGUUCAAGUGGGAAAACAGUGCAGUGUGGGCCAAUGUCUGGGACACGGUCCAGACCAUCAUCCCAUGGAGCACAGGGCCGCGCCACUCAGGCCUCGUUCUGAAGACGAUCAGAGUCAAAGCAGGAGAAACCCAGCAAAGAAUGACAUUUUGUUCAGAAAACACAGAUGACCUACUACUUCGCCCAACCCAGGAAAAAAUCUUCGUGAAAUGUGAAAUAAAGUCUAAAACAUCAAAGCGAAAGAUCAGAUGAGAUUUAAUGAAGACCCAGUGUAAAGAAUAAAUGAAUCUUACUCCUUAUCUGGAAUGGCUGCCUUAUUUAGAAGCCAAAAUUACAUAAAGAAUCUCACACAAAGCUUAAAUAAAGUUUAGAUUUAAGGGGGGUAUGUUUCACUCUCAUAAACUGAGCUUUUAAAAACGAUAUGAUAUAACUAUUUUCCAGUAUCAGUACAACCAAAAAUGUCCCAAUUUUAUCUCUGGUUAAAUGUUAAUAUAUGCAAAUAAGUACAAAUGCAAGAGCCAUUUUAGAUCUGUUGUUCUAAUUUACAAUGUCUUUUAUAAUUAAGUUUCCCACAUGUCCUUGCUAGUUUAUUAUGACCCAUUUUUGAACCAUGCUAGAAAGAUACUUUUUUAUUAGGUAACUAGUGCUUCAAUAAAGCAAGAUUCUAAUUAAUCACCACUAGUUGUGUAUACCAAAUACACAUCCUUUAAGACAAUACAGUUCUUAAAAGAAGAAAAAUUAUAAUUAUUCUAAUAUUUAUACAAAUCAUAUAACGAUUUCACAGAACCAAACACUUACAAGUAGAAUUCUACUAAAACUACUUGUGAUAACAGUGAAAGCUAGACAUGUGGUCAUUUUAAUAAUGGAAUUACAAAUUAAAUAAACAUAAUUAUUAUAUCUUACUAAUGCUUGCAACAAAAGCUAAUUUUAAAAACUUGGAAUGUCUCAAAGCAUUUGCUAUGGACUGAAUGUUUGAGUCACCCCAAAAUUCAUAUGCUGAAAUCUAAUCCCCAAUGUGAUGGUGUUUGGAGGUGGGGCCUUUGGGAGGUGAUCAGGUCAUGAGGGUGGAGCCCUCAUAAGUGGGAUUAGUGCCCUUAUAGGGGAUAAAGGAUCAGAACUCUCUGCCAUGUGCGGAUAUGAGAAGGCAACUAUAUGCAAACCAGGAAGUUGACCCUCACCUGGAAGUAGACUACCAGAUCUGCUGGCACCUUUAUCUUGGACUUCUCAGCUUCCAGAACUGUGAGAAAUAAAUGUUUCUUGUUUAAGCCA